AGCAUAGCGACUCGGAGUCCCCAUGAGGCAGGUUUCCUCUAUUUCUUCCUGACCUGGGGGGCAGCAGGAGGGAUUCCAGGCCUGGUGGACCGCAGUCUAGGGCAGCCUGGUUGCAAGUGUCCUUGGGAGAAACAGGCAUGGAGGGCUGGGCAGACAUAUAUGCAAUACAUACACAGCAGUGUGUGCCCAUGGAGGGGAACCCGUGACCCCUGGCUUAGGACAACCUGCUGAGGUAGAAAGGACCUUGCCCAGGGAGUUGAGAUUGCUUCUCACUGUGGGAUCUUGGAUAACUCACCUCGCCUUCCGAGGCCUCAGUUUCCCGAUCUGUAAAAUGGCGUGAGGGUAAUUACUGUCCUGUUUGCCCCCACGAGGCUAUUGUGGAGAUGAAAUGAGAUAAUGAAAUAGAAGGGCUGAGAAAAAACUGUAGACUGCGGUGCAGCCGUGAAGCACUAUAUGGUGAUACUAAGCACCACUUCCGCAGGCUUUAGCCCCUGUCUCUGCCUCAAGUGUCUGUCACAGAGGGGAUGGGGUGGGCCAGCCUCUCCCAGCCCCUCUCUGGGCCCCCCUUGCCUACUACCCCCCCCUUUUGGAGCUGGGACAUUCCAGUCCCAUUCCUUAGGGGCAGCUGCAGACACGCCCCUUAGCAGAGCUGAUCCCCCAGCAGGUGGUGGGACCUUUCCCUGGGGCCAGGGCUCAGGAGGGGCUGACUGUAGCCAGGGCAGGCAGCACUCCUGCCCAUGUGGGGACUGGAAUGUCCCACCCCAGAGGAGAUGCAAGGUGGGAUCCGAGAGGACUUCUAAUCCUGGAGCCUGUGUGCUUUCUCCCCUGCGGCUGAACGUGACCUUAGGCGUGUUACUUCACUUUCUGAACCUCAGUUUCCUCUUGUGAAGUGGGGGAUGACAGAACUCAUCUCCUGUGUGUCUUGUGAGGAUGUGAUAGUGCCCUUUGGCGUGACCCAAAAGGGCACCAACAGGCUCUGGGACGCCCCCCUCAAAGAAAGCGCGUCCUCUCCUUCUUUGCUUCCUGGCCAGGGCAGCUGUGUCUUCCAUCUCCACCAAGGAUUGGUCCGAAAGCAAUUCCUCUCCGUGUUCAGAGAUUCCAGUGCUGCCUGCUAAUCUUGGGGACUGGAGAGGGGUGAGGGGACUGGUGGCGGGGAGCAGGAGUGAAGAGGCCUUACUGGGGCUAGCCAGGACCUGUGGAGAAUGUGGCUUGAAUGUCCCAGCCCAAAUCUAGCCAGCUGUGUGGCUGGGGGUUUGCCGCUCCCAGCUCAGGGAAGCCCAGGCACUUGGCUUGUCCCCUACCCUUCUCUCCACGACCCGUGCAGGGUCCCCGGCUUUUUGCUCUGAUGUUCCAGUGAGGCUGCAAGGCACUUGCUGUCCUCCCUCCCUCCUCCCCCACCAAAUCCCCUCCGCCUGCACAGCUGCCCUGCCCAGCUGCCCUGCCCGGAGCAGGCAAUCCCUGGGCUUCCAAGCAACAGGAAGGAAGGAAUGUAUGUGUUGGGGGAGGGGGUGGAGGUAGGAUGGACCCCUUUAGGAAAAGAGACUGUCCCCACUCUGUGACAUACGCAGGGAGGAGUGUCCUGAAAGCUGGGGGCCCCCGCCCUGCUGGGGGAGCUGAUAAUCCAGUCAGUCAGCCAGGAGGGGCACAGUGGGGACGGUGGGGGGCCUAAGGAGAGACAAAGGGAAGGGGCUGUCUGCUGCUCCUUCACUAGCCUGGGGGCUGGGAAGGACACUAGGUCAUCAUGCCACUGGGCUGCUCCUGCUUUGUCAGUGUGUCCUGUGGGUGACCUUGUGCACAGCUGUAUGAUUGUGUUUGCUGCUGGACGUGACCGUCUGCACCGUGUCCUCUAACAUGGGCUCUCUGUGCUGCUGGGUGGGGCUGACAUGUGGCACACCGUGGCGUGUGUGGUUGUAUGCGCUGUUGCGGCCGGUGGCUACCUCUAGCUCAGGGACUUUCCCUGGACCUGCGAUGCCUCGUGGGGAACCUGGGGGUCGGUUAUCUCCUCGAGACAGGAAGUGAGCAUCUGCCCACCGGAAGCUGAGGCGGUGUGCAUUUGGGGUGAGGUGGGCGUAUUUGGCACUGCUGCCAACGUCCCCGCCCCCAGGGCCACACAGGGCUUACAUUUCAUAAGCCCUUUCCCCUCCAUCUCUGACUGUCAGUAAUCCUUUGAGGAAAGCCGGGCAGGCGGGGUCUUUCCCACUUCAUUUUUUUUUCCUUUUUAAAAAUAAAUAGAGAUGGGGUCUCGCUAUGUUGCUAAGGGUGGUUUCAAACUCCUGGGGUCAAGUGAUCCUCCUGCCUCAGCCUCCCAAAGUGCUGGGAUUACAGGUGUGAGCCACCAUGCCUGGCCCUUUCCCGCUUCAGAGAUGCAGAAACUGAGGCAUGGCAAAAGGCGGAGCAUUUGUGUCUGGGGUCCCCUGGAGAGAGUGAGGGCAGGCUGGAGAGCAGGUCUCUGCUGUCCCCUCCCCAAGAAGCAGCAACAGGAGUUGAGCGUGCUUGUGGACAAACCACAUCUCUGGCUGGAUGGGCUUGUCGUGGCAAGGAGGUAUCAGAUGAGGAGGCAGGAUGCUUCCAUUCUAAUACUUUUGGCUGUAGGGACCAAUCCUAGGUCCCACUAGACAUUGGGCAGCCAUGACCAGCUACGACCUUGGGCAAGUCACUUCACCUUUCUGAGCCCCACUGACCUUUAAGAAGGGUCAAUAGCUGGGCACAGUGUCACGCACCUGUGUUUUUAGCUACUCAGGAGGCUGAAGUGGGAAGAUGGCUUGAUCCUAGGAGUUCGAGGCUGCAGUGGGCCAUGGUUGCACUACUGUAGUCCAGCCUGGGUGACAGAGUGAAGAGCAAGACCCUGUCUCAAAAAAAAAAAAAAAAAAAAAGAAGGGACAAUAACUCUGUCACAGGACUCAGCAGGACCCGUAUGCAGGGCCAAGUCGCUGUAGGAACCCAUCCCCUGUGAUUCCUUACCUGGAUGCAUCUCCUAUGUAGCCUGCAACGUGCGUUCUCAGGGGCUGGGCUGGGUGGGGUGUGCAAACCCGGAUUCGCCCCAUCCUGGGUUUGGGGGUUGGUUGGGGGAGAGCUGAGGUCAUUUUUGCACAGGGUGAGGUGAGGCUGUGGGGUUGGGGCAGGUCCCCCUCCCGGAGAGCUUUGUCUUCCACAAACACAAAACCUGGAAAUGGUUGAGGAAGAUGGAACCUCCUAACGACCAUUGUUCGGGGGCAGGAGUGGGUGCCCGGAAGCAUGGGUGGUAGUAGGGGACCCACAGCUGCAGCUGGCCUGCUGGGCUUCUGUUCGAGAAUGGGAGCAGCUGCUCAGGGGUGGGAGGCAGAGAAGGUGGCAUUUGUUCACUCGGCCAGACCUUUCUGCACGCCCGCUCCAUGCUGGGCACUGGGCUGUGCAGAGGAUCCCCAGGGGACUAGGUACCAGCCCUGCCUCCAGAGUGUGUGGCCCAGCACAGGUGGAAGGUGGUCCGUCAGCCUAGUCCCUUGGUGAUGUUUGUGUGCCUGGCUGAGCUCGGCUCCAGCCAGCCUGUUGACCCUGGCUGUGGCCCAGGCCCUGAACUGGGUGCUCUGUCAUGUUAUCCCACCCCAUCCUCCCAGCAUCCCAGUGAUAAGUGUUAUUGUCGCCAGGGUGUGUGUGCGGAAGUCCAGGCUCACUGAGGUUAGUGGCUUGGCCGGGGUCACACACCGAUUGGUUCCGCCAGGGUUAGGAUUUGGGACCCACCCUGCCGGGUGGUGGGCUUUGGAAUAAGAGCAUAUACAGGGGCUGGAGUGAGUCCAGCUGCCCCUUCCCUCCUCCACCCACCACUGCCCAGACGGGAACACCUGUCCCGGAAACUGUGGCCAUUGUUCACGUCAUCCUUCCUCCUUUUGGGCCCUUCCUGUUUGUAUCCCUCCCACUGUAGCCCCCAACCCUCCCCCCCAUGCCAGAUGUUUCCCUUGGGGAGCUUUGCCCUUUGCAGGAAGAGGGCCUGCAGGGGUUACCCCUCUCCCAUGGGAAGGAGGGUCUCACUGGCCUUGGGUCUCUGUGCCUUCUCCCCACCCCACAGAUUUGGUGGGGAACAUGGCAGGAGGGUAAGCAAGGUCAGGUUCAGCCAGGCUGAGUUUUCUUUUUUUUUUUUUUUUGAGAUGGAGUCUCCCUCUGUCGCCCAUGCUGGAGUGCAGUGGUGCGAUCUCGGCUCACUGCAAGCUCUGCCUCCCAGGUUCAUGCCAUUCUCCAGCCUCAGCCUCCCGAGUAGCUGGGACUACAGGCGCCCACCACCAUGCCCGGCUAGUUUUUGUAUUUUUAGUAGAGAUGGGGUUUCACAGUGUUAGCCAGGAUGGUCUGCGUUUCCUGACCUUGUGAUCUGCCUGCCUUAGCCUCCCAAAGUGCUGGGAUUACAGGCGUGAGCCACCGCGCCCGGCCAAGUUUGUCUUCCUUAGCCCUGUGCGGGCCCAGUGCUGGGAGGACGGCUCCUGUCCUGCUGCUUCCAGGCCUAUCCCCUCCCGGUACUUCUGAAUCCCACACAGGCCCCGAGGUGGAGCUGGCCCUUCGGUGCUCGGCUGGGGCACCAUUGCUCUUCCUUAGACUCAGUCCAGCAAGUGACAGAUGGGCAGGUGGCUUUGGGGCUUGUACUUCUUUCUCUUGCCAGUCUAGGGAUCCUGUCCCGGGGUUCUCUCUUGGACCCACAUCUGCCUUACCUGGGCCUGGGCAAGGUUGUGGGGAGCUACAGGGAGCAAGUACCUUGUUUUCAGGCCCCAGGGAAGUUGGGCAGCCAGUGCUCACCUGCCCCUAAUGGAGCCUCCCAAUUCCCAGAAGCAGCUGCCUGUACCCUGUUGAAACUUCAUGGCCACAGCCCCAGGCCCUGCUGGCAUUGCCAUGGGCAGCGUGGGCAGCCUGUUGGAACGGCAGGACUUCUCCCCUGAAGAGCUGCGGGCGGCACUUGCCGGGUCUCGGGGCUCCCGCCAGCCUGAUGGGCUCCUCCGGAAGGGCUUGGGCCAGCGUGAGUUCCUCAGCUACCUGCACCUCCCCAAGAAGGACAGCAAGAGCACCAAGAACACCAAGCGGGCCCCUCGGAACGAGCCUGCCGACUAUGCCACCCUCUACUACCGGGAACAUUCUCGCGCGGGUGACUUCAGCAAGACCUCGCUGCCAGAACGGGGUCGCUUUGACAAGUGCCGCAUUCGCCCCUCAGUGUUCAAGCCUACGGCGGGCAACGGGAAAGGCUUCCUAUCCAUGCAAAGUCUGGCGUCCCACAAAGGCCAGAAGCUGUGGCGCAGCAAUGGCAGCCUGCACACGCUGGCCUGCCACCCGCCCCUGAGCCCCGGGCCCCGGGCCAGCCAGGCCCGGGCACAGCUGCUGCACGCCCUCAGCCUAGAUGAGGGCGGCCCUGAGCCCGAGCCCAGCCUGUCCGACUCCUCCAGUGGGGGUAGUUUUGGUCGCAGUCCUGGUACUGGCCCUAGCCCCUUCAGCUCCUCCCUUGGCCACCUUAACCACCUCGGGGGCUCCCUGGACCGGGCCUCUCAAGGACCCAAGGAGGCUGGGCCACCAGCUGUGCUGAGCUGCCUGCCCGAGCCACCACCCCCCUACGAGUUCUCCUGCUCCUCUGCCGAGGAAAUGGGAGCCGUGCUGCCCGAGACCUGUGAGGAGCUCAAGAGGGGCCUUGGCGAUGAGGACGGCUCCAACCCCUUCACGCAGGUGCUGGAGGAGCGCCAGCGGCUGUGGCUGGCUGAGCUGAAGCGCCUGUAUGUGGAGCGGCUGCACGAGGUGACCCAGAAGGCUGAGCGCAGCGAGCGCAACCUCCAGCUGCAGCUGUUUAUGGCUCAGCAGGAGCAGCGGCGCCUGCGCAAGGAGCUGCGGGCUCAGCAGGGCCUGGCUCCGGAGCCUCGGGCCCCCGGCACCCUCCCAGAGGCUGACCCCAGUGCACGACCAGAGGAGGAAGCCCGAUGGGAGGUGUGCCAGAAGACAGCAGAGAUUAGCCUCUUGAAGCAGCAGCUGCGUGAAGCCCAGGCGGAACUGGCCCAGAAGCUGGCGGAGAUCUUCAGUCUGAAGACACAACUUCGGGGCAGCCGGGCACAAGCCCAGGCUCAGGACGCAGAGCUGGUCCGGCUGCGCGAGGCUGUGCGCAGCCUGCAGGAGCAGGCCCCUCGGGAGGAAGCCCCAGGCAGCUGUGAGACUGAUGACUGCAAGAGCAGGGGCCUGCUAGGGGAGGCAGGAGGCAGCGAGGCCAGAGACAGUGCUGAGCAGCUGCGGGCUGAGCUGCUGCAGGAGCGACUUCGGGGCCAGGAGCAGGCGCUGCGCUUUGAGCAGGAGCGGCGGACUUGGCAGGAGGAGAAGGAGCGCGUGCUGCGCUACCAGCGGGAGAUCCAGGGAGGGUACAUGGACAUGUACCGCCGCAACCAGGCACUGGAGCAGGAACUGCGGGCACUGCGGGAGCCCCCCACACCCUGGAGUCCCCGGCUCGAGUCCUCCAAGAUCUGAGGCCAGCAGAGCGAGCUGACAGCAGCAACACUGUCAGAAGGUGCCCUGAGACGGCCGGCUCAGCCUUCCCUUGCACUGGUUGGGGUGGAACCUGCAGAGGCCAGCCCGGGGCUGGGGAGGCGCAAGGAGAGGAGGGAUCCAGUGGGGCCGUGGGCUGGGUAGGGUGCCUUGGCAGGAGCCAGGACAAGGCCCUCCUGGCAGAGGAGCACCUAGGCAGGGCCCAGCCCUGCUUCCUGGAGUGGAUGUGGCCCAGAGAAGGAGGCUGGGGGAUCACCAGCCCCAAGGUCCCGAAGGGCAGGUCAGAGGGAGAGAGGCUGGAGACCUGGGCUGGGGCCUUCCUCCAGGGAAGGAGGCUGGGGUGGGAACACUGGCCUCCCCCAGAAUAAAACCAUGUUUUCUACCAGAGGCUCAGAAUACGCUGAGCCUGUGACCAGAGGAUGAUGGAUGGUCGGGAUUGAGGCUGUUGACCUGGGCAGUAGCUCCUCCCAUGGCCAGUGGUCAGUGGGAGGGUGUGCCCUGCGCCUGUCUGCAUGGCCACUGGGCAUGUGUGUUGGGAGCAGAGGAGUCCUACUCCUUGCCUCAGCCCCACACGGUUCCUUAGCUGCCGUGUGGGCUGAAAUUCCUUUCUUUAGCACCAGUGGAGUUUUCAGAAGGAACAACACCAGGGAAUGCCAAAAAAACAAAGGGCAAGUCAACCAAGGCAUUUUGAGAACAUGAAAUGUCUUCUUGGUGGGAAGGCUGGGCCCCAGGAGUAUCCACAGGCUCAGGCCAUGCCCCUCCCCGCACCCACCUCCUGUCUCCCUCCCUCCCUCCAUAGGAGUGGGGGGCCCCUAGAAGUGCUCUGCCUCAUUCCCUGUUCGUAGGAAGGUGCAGGAGAGGAGGUGGGCAAGCUUAUGGGUUUCUUGGUAAAGAGCCUUUACCACAGCAAGGAAUGGGAACAUUUCCCCAUCAGCAACGGGGCUCUAGGGCAUUAUUAAGUAGGGGUGAAAUAUGAUUGAUUUGCAUUCUGGAAAGCUCUCCCAGGAGGAAGCAUUCCCCACCCCACCUUGCCUCUGUCCUGCGCUGGGCUCCAGGACGGUCAGUCCUCCCGGAUCCCUGCUCUCAGCUAAGGCUGGUCCCUAAAACCCACACCUGCCUUUGGUCUCUCAGAGGCCUGGCUUGCCCUCUGGGCCUUUGCUCCCCCGCUGGGUGCCCGGCCUGGAACACAGGUUCUGUCUGGCUGUGUGAGUGGCGUCUCUCCCUUCCUUUGAGGGAAGCUCAGCUUUCUUACGCGCUCAUCGUUGGACGGGCUGCCAUGCAUUGCGUGCUUACUGGGCGCCAGGUGCUGUGCUGGGCCCUUGUGAGUGUGGGGGCACAGGCUGAAUUAGAUGAGCUCCUGCCGCAGGGGGCCCUGCACACUGAUGUCAGCUCACCAGUCUCUUCCCUGACAGGGCAGCUCAGGGAACUUCUGAGAAGUUAUCUGCAGAGAGCCCCACCUCACUCCCUUUGGCUACCCUGGCCGUGCCUGGCAGCCCCUCAGGCCCCACAGGUGGGUCCUGGUUGUGAAGUGGAGUUAGUGCACAUGGAUGUCAGGGGACGGGUGUGAGGCAUGAGCUGGGGGGGCCCCCUUUUUCAGGGCAGAGAAUGAGGCGUGUGCACUGUCUGCUGUGGGGAUGGUGUGUUUAUGGCCAUGUAAGUGGCAGGUGUGUGUAAAGAUGUGCUUGUGGGUGGUGGGUGUGUCUGAGGGGGUGUGUUUGGGAGCCUGGCCUCCAAAAGCCAGUGUCUGGGUUGGAGACAGUGCAGGCCCCUUCUUGGCCCCACCCUCUACCCCAUUCCUUCCUGUCAGCCCCAGUCUGUCUUGGCACUGGCCAGGCUUGGGUGGAGCCUGUGUCCCAGACAGAUCCCCUAGGCCUAUCUGAGACCCAUACAGGCCCACACCUGAGCUCCUGUCUGCCUGAGGAGGGAAAGGGGGAGUGGCCAGGUCAGGCAGGCCAGUCGUCUACACACCCCCUUGGUACCCAUUCCCAUUUCACAAACUCCUCCAAACCCCAAACCCCAAACGGAAAUCUCUGGGACAAUGGCUCCUCCAGAGGGCCCCUCAGAGCCAGGUGCUGGCCAGAUGCCUUGAUCACAGCCUCCAUGGCCAGGGGCCUGUCAAGCCAGGGGCCCACACACCUGGUGCCAGGGUCCACCUUGGUAUACCAGCUCGGCAGAACAGUUCCCCACCCAGCGAUUAGGGAGCUGGGCUGGCCAGUACAGCCAGUGGGGAGUGGGUGGGAGGCACCAAAACUUGGCAGCUGUGCCAGAAACCAAAGCCAGGCCCAGAUGUAGGGGGAGGGCACGAGAGCUGAACCUGAGCCUGGGGCGUCUCGGAGCUGGAUCCCCGUCAGCUCAUCCAGGCUGGACAAACCAGUUCCUGGGUCCCCCAGCCGGCUGGGUGGCUCUGGGGCCAACCGACCACAGGUGUCACUGAUCACAGGUGUCACCGUAGUGGCUACCACCUCAGGGCAGCCCCUCCCUCCAGCUGGCGGGGCCUCAGCUUCCCAGCUGCCCUGGCUUAGCCUUCCCUGCAGCCCCUCCCCAACAGGCUUGGUCCGGGCAGCCUGCUCUGCGGAAGGUGGCAGCCUCCUGGUGCUGGGCUCCCUGCCUCUGGGGCCUCCAGUCCUUCACUCAGUGUCAUCCCUUCCAGCAGCUCCCUGGGCCUCUUGGUCCAUCCCUUCAGGCUUCUGACACACUAGUGGCCUCGAGUCACUGAUAGUGGUGCCUCCUCCUUACCUUGGCAAGCCCUUGUAGCCCUCUGAGCCCUCAUCCUGCAGGCAGAGCCCCUCAGUGCUCUGAGAAACCUGCCCUGAACUCACCGCCUCCCCUGCCUGGGCACUCCCUCCUCCCUGCGCCCACAGCCCCCAUGCCAAUCUCCGUCAGCUCUUUCUGUGCUGCUGUAAUUGUUGGUUUGCCUGUCUCCUUUGAGCUGUGGGCAUUGCCGGGGUAGGGUGGUGUCUUCACCACAGCUCCAGAAGGCACUGGUGGGAUGUGGAGUCAGGAGCAACCAGAGACCCCCCAAUACUAGAAUGGGUUUGAGCUUGGGGUGGGGUGGAUGGGGAAGACUUACUCUGAAUGUUCGUUCACCAUCCGUGGGCACCAGGUCUGUGCCAAGCACAGGGACUCCAGGGGCAGCUGCCAUUCGUUCCAGUGAUGUAUUUGGGGCCUUCUCAGGUGAGGAAGCCAAGGUGGCCAAGGCCCUCGGUCCCCUGCCCUGAUAGGGCUUACCUGUGGGUGGGGGAGGGAGACCACACAUGUCAGAGGUAGUGAAGGCCGCUCCAAAUAGUGACUGGGGCCAGGCAGGCGGAAAAGAGAACAGAAGAGAAUCCAGAAGUGUUCAGACAGAACUAGGGACAACAGAGGGGCCUCCAUGGUGGCAUGGGUCAGCAGAGCAUGGAGCAGGCAGAGGAAGCCUAUCUGUGGGGCUGGGUACAUUUCUCUGAGACUCACGGAAUGUAAGUGUUGAGGUUUCUGCAAAGAGGGCGCAGGCCCUGCAGUGACGGUUCAGAUAUUGAUAACCCAUCCCCCUUGGCAGGUGGGGGCUUAGGCAUCCAUAUUGGAUUCAGAAAAGAAAAAGAAUGAUGCUUCUUGCAACAAAAACAAAAGUGAUUAUGUCACGAGAGGAGAGGCUGGAGGGCCAUGGGAGUUCCCAGCUGGCUCACUCAUCCGUCCAGGAGGUGGGUCUCAUGGUUUCAUUUUGCUUUGGGCUUACUUAGAGUUUUGGCAAAUGCAGAGUUAUGUAACGAACCCAACAAUGAAGAUACAGUUCUGUCACCCCCCCAGCAUUCUCCUGUGGCCCUCUAGUCCACCCCCCGCCCCACCCCAGCCCCUGGCAACCACUGAUCUGCUUUCACAAUAACCGUAUGGGGUUUUUUCUCUUUCCUUUUUUGUGAGCGGUAUUUAAUUCCUUUGCUCUAAUAUGUAAUAUUAGAACAUAUUACAAAGUAGCAAGAAAAAUACGACAUUGGUGUAAAAAUAAUCUACACCUCAUGGAAAGAAUGAAGAGCCAGAAAUAGAUUCUAUUCUGUAGAAAAUCUUACACAAUAAAGGACUUCAAAAUAA